UGGCCCAAGACCUCCAUAAUGUUAUCACUAGUGUUUCAAAGGAAUCCUCUGAGAAUAUUAUCUCAGAUAAUCAGAGCGUGCCUGAGACAUAAGUCAAAGAGUAACCAGUCUGUCACCAGAUAGAUUGCUGCUUCCUUUCUUCUUGCGUAUCCUAAUGGGAGUGGAGGGAAUUGCCUCCCAACUCUGGGGUAAGCUUUUUUUUCCCCCAGGUUUUCAGUGAGUGAUCAAAGAAUCAGAGCUGCAAAACUACUCUGGAACCUUUAAGACCCAUUGUAUAUCACACAAACAGAAUACAUGAGUUAAGUUUCAUACUGUAGGGAAUCCACCCUUUGUCCUGCCCUUCUGCUUGACAUUUUUCUGUACUAGAGCUCUUCUAUCUUCAGUCUUCUGUAUAAGGUAAAGUCUCAUGCAUAAGGCAGCAAUCCCAUGUUUAUACAUAAUUCCUCAACUAUAUUUUAGUUAGUAGCAGUAUCCCUUAACCUAGCACUGCCUUGCCGCUAUGCCUUUCAACUCCAAGACGCCAGUGUAAUUCUCUACGAUGGGCCCUCUCUCUACAUUGUGCAACACCUUCCCAAGAGCAAGGGGCAGGGUCUGGCCCUUCCAGCCUUAUCAAACCUUUCUUAUUACAUCUGGAGUAUUCUAGUAUUCAAGCCCUCAAGGAAUGGGAAUUGUGAUGUUUGUGGUGAAAUUAAAGCCAUAAUAGAAUGGAAACAAAGUAGUUCUUUAAAUACAUCCCCUGUAAACCAUAUUAAAAUGAAACUUUGACCCUGGAUAAUCAAGUUAUUCUACUUUUACAUAUUUUUUUUUCAAAAUUUGAUGAUCAGGAGAAUAGAAUUUAAUGAAUUUAAUUUUUUCAACUCUGUAUUUCUAUAAAUUGGGUAAAAGUAAAUCUUCUUGAGUUAGAUUGCUACAUAAGCCCCGUGCUAUGCUGCCUCUGAAAAAUAAUUAUGCGUAUUCCUGGUUAGGGGCUCCCGGUGUAUGGUAAUUAGACAGCUGGGUUAAAUGAAUGAUAAUCAAUUUUCCUGACUUUUCUUAAGCAUUAAAGUCUCUUUGGGUACUUUAUUUUACUAGCUGAGAAUAAUAAAAAGAGCAUUUUAAAUGUUAGGCAGUGAAAAUCAGGACCAUAACACUAAACUAUUUAAGUUUCCAUGUGAGAUUAUUUUCUUUCAUUAGCUACAGGGACAUCUAAAACCUUAAAGUAGGACUUAAUUAAAUUUAUUUUGUUUGUUUAAAGUACUUUUUGUUUUGCUUUUAAAAUGAAUCUCAGUAAUUACCAAAAAGAAAAAUGAACUUAAUUUCUUUAUUAUGACCUUCAGCCAGAAUGAUGAACGGUAUUUAAUUCUGGAAAAGUAUUCUUUAAAAGCCAGUAUGUUAAAUCACUGACUUCUCUCUUAGACUAGAACUUACAUAUCAGCAUUAAAACAUACUCUGAAUGCUGGAUAGCCCUGAUUUAUUAUUAUUAUUAAUUAAUUAAUUUAUUGAGAUGGAGUUUUGCUCUUGUUGCCUAGGCUGGAGUGCAAUGGCGCGAUCUUAGUUCACUGCAACCUCCGCCUCCCAGGUUCAAGCGAUUUUCCUGCCUCAGCCUCCUGAGUAGCUGGGAUUACCGGCAUGUGCCACCAUGCCUGGCUAACUUUGUAUUUUUAGUAGAGAUGGGGUUUCUCCAUGUUGGUCAGGCUGGUCUCGAACUCCUGACCUCAGGUGAUUUGCCCACCUCCGUCUCCCAAAGUGCUGGGAUUACAGGCAUGAGCCACCGCGCCCAGCCAAUAAGCCUGAAUUAUACAAAAGAUAAAAAUAAUUUUUUUUCUUCUAAUAUGCUAAUCUUAAUUGUCAACAUACUAUCCUGGUGUCUAGAAAAUACCUGUAAAGGAAUGUGAAUUACAGCAGUUCUUAUCUCAUUUUCUAUAUUACUGUGUUCUUUACACCAAAAUGUACAAAUACCACCUACCAAAGUUUACACCUCUCAAAAUAAGGCUAUGGCCAUCAUGCUUUAAAAGCAUGGCUCUGUGUGCUUGUUCACUCUGUGUCCUCUGCCAUAUGCCUACACUUAAAAUAACCUGGGGAUAUUUAAAACAUUCCAAAGCCCAAGCCAUACCACAGACCAAUUAAAUUAUAUGCCUGAGACACAGGCAUCAAUAGUUUUUGAAAGUUUCUAGGUAAUUCCAACGUGCUUGCAAGUUUGAGAGCACUGUCUCAACCAACUUGUUCUCAGGCAAACUUCUGUUUAUCCUUCCCUUCUCAGUUCACAGGGGAUGUUUGAUGCUCUCCCUCCCUAGGCCUUCUCACUAUUCUUCCUGCGUAUCUCUACCAUAGCAUGAACUAACUAUGUUGUAACUGUUAACUCACGUGUCUGUUCCCCUAAUCUACUAUAAGAUUAAGGAGUAUUUUUAUUUUUGAAUCUCUGAAUCUAACCCUUUGCCUGGUGCAUGGGAGAACCCAAUAAAUUCAUAGAAUGAAUAACCUGUUCCUAAGAAAAACAAAAGCAAAAAUGUAGAGUUGUGUUAAUAUUUAAAUGCCAUGGAAAAAGUAAUUGCUUAGGAUGUGUUUAAAAUAAUGUUUCCCUGGUGGGCAAUGUCCCAUAUUUAGAAAAACAUCUCAUCAUAUUAGUGAAAAUAAAACAUCCCAACAUUAAGAAGAAACAUAAAAUAUAACUUUGAAUUAUUACCCACACAGUUGCAUUCUUUAUUGUAAUAAGCACAGAAAAACGUUUUAAACGUUUUCUGUGAUAAGAAAUAUCUAAAACAACACAUCCUUUCUCAGCUCCCCUUCCAUCUUUACUAGAUUAUGUAUUACUUCCCCAAUCAGUCCUUUCAGAAUUUGAUGAUGUUACAGGAGUUUAUAUAACUGAUUUUAAGAGUUUAAAAUACUUAGUUUGCAAAAUAUUUUAACUAAGAGUCUCUGUUUAAUGUGGUAUUUAUACUGUUAAUAUUAUCACUAUGAUUCAGAAAAUAUUCACAUAGUGAAUUUUCCUACAAUAUAAUUCUGGACAACAAGCCCACUCUUAAACACACUUUUUUUUUUAAACUGUUCCAAAUAUUUUGCUAUUUGUUUUACCUAAUUAUAUUUGCAGCAAUGUUUCACGCCUACCAAUAUGUUGUUGUUUAUCUGUUAGAUUUUGAUUCAUGAAACCUGAAAAUAAAUCAGAUUUAGGAACUGUUUUCCAAGAUAGUGAUAUAUUAUUCAUUUAUCUAAUUUAUCUUUACACAUGAAAUGCCGGAUUAUCUCAGUAGGUACCAAAUUAAUUUAAGACCUUACCAAGUAGUAUACAAUAUGCACUCAUUCUGAUGCAUAUAAAAGACAAAAAUGAGAAAAAAAGUGCAAUCCUCUACCUUUAAAUGCCUACACUGUCCUCAACUAUUGUUAUCCAAUUUUUAACUUUAGUACAUUAAGUACAGCUACAUUUUUUUUUUUCUUUUUCAGACAGGGUCUCACUCUGUCACCCAGGCUAGAGUCCCGUGGUGUAAUCAUAAUUCACUGUGGCCUCAACCUCCUAGGCCCAAGCCAUCCUCCCACCUCAGCCUCCUGAGUAGCUGGGGCUACAGGCAUGGGCCACCAUGCCCGGAAAAUUUAUUUAUUUUUUAUUUUUAGUAGAAACAAGGUCUGGCUAUGAUGCCCAGGCUGUCUUGAACUCCCGGCCUCAAACGAUCCUGUCACCUCGGCCUCCCAAAGUGCUGGAGUACCGCUAAUUUAAAAGGCAGUCAUUGAAACAUAUUUCUUGUUCUCUUUUGCAUCAUGGAGUUAUGACUUUAAAUCAUAAGUACAGUAUCCUUAGAAACUGCCCAGUUUUAUCAGAAAUAAGUUCUGAAUGUAUUGUCAAUUGUGAAAAGACAAAAGAUCACAGUUCCUAAUAUUCAGUUCUAAUGGCAUGGUUCCCCAAAAUGUAAAAGCUGUGACUGAGACAAUUAUUUCAAGAGAGCUUCAGCUGUAAAUAAACACAAAACUGAAUUCCUUUGCCAUGCAAACAAGAGGCACACUUUCAACCAGUAACAGCUGGCUUCAUAUAUUCAUCUUUGGAUGAAAAGAGCAGGGCAGUUUUUUUUUUUUUUUUUUUUUUGAGACGGAGUCUCGCUCUGUCGCCCAGGCUGGAGUGCAGUGGCGGGAUCUCGGCUCACUGCAAGCUCCGCCUCCCGGGUUCACGCCAUUCUCCUGCCUCAGCCUCCCAAGUAGCUGGGACUACAGGCGCCCGCCACUACGCCCGGCUAAUUUUUUGUAUUUUUAGUAGAGACGGGGUUUCACCGUUUUAGCCGGGAUGGUCUCGAUCUCCUGACCUCGUGAUCCGCCCGCCUCGGCCUCCCAAAGUGCUGGGAUUACAGGCGUGAGCCACCGCGGAGCAGGGCAGUUUUAAAGUUGACUUCUGAGAGCAUCAGAUUUUGGAUAGUGUCCUUUCUCAGGUCCUGUUUCCUUGUCUCCUCAUCCCAUUUUAAAAGCCAGACACAUAAACCCCGGCACUCCUUUAGCGAAGGGCUCAGUGAGGGCGUUUUUGCCACCCGUGGCCAGGGGUCAUUGGGUCAGCAAAGUCAGAGGAAACCUAGAAAGGCAGAAGCCCAGGAGGUUGACGCCCUGCGGGUCUAGGGGCCAGGUGCUGGGUGUCUCUCCUUUCGUGUGCGGUUCCCAGCAGCAGGUCCUGGUGGGCGCAGACUGACCGGAGAGGUGUGGCUCGCCCCCUCCCCAGACCCCGAGGUGGCAAUGAAACCUCCAUCUCCUGGCUUGAUUCCUUGUGCUAUAAAAAAUCUUCCACUGGCCCUUUGCAUCUCUCGCCCUCCAUCCCCCAAAGCCACUAUCGGGAGGGGACAAAAAUAAUUUCUGAGGGGCCAUGGGCACUAAAACCACAGCAGACAGAGGCUGUGUCUACCUGAGGAACUGGAGAGGUAGAAUUAGAGGGGGAGGCUGGGCAUCCUCGGCGGCGCCCCCUCCAUCCAGCGUGAAACCCACGAGGCGCGGCGUCUCGAGUGGCGGGCGGGCAGGGGGCUGCAGGAUUCACGAAGCCACCUCCGCCGGGGACCGCCUUCUCUCGGAGUGGCCUCCCCUCCGGCGUUCCGCUUUAGUAAGACGACACUCAGGCCAAACAGCCGCCCCCGGCCAGCCCGACUCGGCUCUGGAGGGAGCGCCCCGAGGGAGUCCAGCCGGAGGCGGAGAAGGCCACUCGGCCAGAAGCUAUGAAACCCACGUAGUCGAACACCGUGAUGCUUCUCCUGCAGGGCGUGUGAUGAGGAGGCGAGCUUGGCUUUGGAGUGCUGGGAACCUGAGGAAUUGCCAAGGACCCAGAGCCCAGCCCUGACCACCAGAGUGCCCAAAACACAAUGAACAAAUUGAAUUUUCAUAACAACAGAGUCAUGCAAGACCGCCGCAGUGUGUGCAUUUUCCUUCCCAACGAUGAAUCUCUGAACAUCAUCAUAAAUGUUAAGAUUCUGUGUCACCAGUUGCUGGUCCAGGUUUGUGACCUGCUCAGGCUAAAGGACUGCCACCUCUUUGGACUCAGUGUUAUACAAAAUAAUGAACAUGUGUAUAUGGAGUUGUCACAAAAGCUUUACAAAUAUUGUCCAAAAGAAUGGAAGAAAGAGGCCAGCAAGGUACGACAAUACGAAGUCACUUGGGGUAUCGACCAAUUUGGGCCUCCUAUGAUCAUCCACUUCCGUGUGCAGUACUAUGUGGAAAAUGGCAGAUUGAUCAGUGACAGAGCAGCAAGAUACUAUUAUUACUGGCACCUGAGAAAACAAGUUCUUCAUUCUCAGUGUGUGCUCCGAGAGGAGGCCUACUUCCUGCUGGCAGCCUUUGCCCUGCAGGCUGAUCUUGGGAACUUCAAAAGGAAUAAGCACUAUGGAAAAUACUUCGAGCCAGAGGCUUACUUCCCAUCUUGGGUUGUUUCCAAGAGGGGGAAGGACUACAUCCUGAAGCACAUUCCAAACAUGCACAAAGAUCAGUUUGCACUAACAGCUUCCGAAGCUCAUCUUAAAUAUAUCAAAGAGGCUGUCCGACUGGAUGACGUCGCUGUUCAUUACUACAGAUUGUAUAAGGAUAAAAGGGAAAUUGAAGCAUCGCUGACUCUUGGAUUGACCAUGAGGGGAAUACAGAUUUUUCAGAAUUUAGAUGAAGAGAAACAAUUACUUUAUGAUUUCCCCUGGACAAAUGUUGGAAAAUUGGUGUUUGUGGGUAAGAAAUUUGAGAUUUUGCCAGAUGGCUUGCCUUCUGCCCGGAAGCUCAUAUACUACACGGGGUGCCCCAUGCGCUCCAGACACCUCCUGCAACUUCUGAGCAACAGCCACCGCCUCUAUAUGAAUCUGCAGCCUGUCCUGCGCCAUAUCCGGAAGCUGGAGGAAAACGAAGAGAAGAAGCAGUACCGGGAAUCUUACAUCAGUGACAACCUGGACCUCGACAUGGACCAGCUGGAAAAACGGUCGCGGGCCAGCGGGAGCAGUGCGGGCAGCAUGAAACACAAGCGCCUGUCCCGUCAUUCCACCGCCAGCCACAGCAGUUCCCACACCUCGGGCAUUGAGGCAGACACCAAGCCCCGGGACACGGGGCCAGAAGACAGCUACUCCAGCAGUGCCAUCCACCGCAAGCUGAAAACCUGCAGCUCAAUGACCAGUCAUGGCAGCUCCCACACCUCAGGGGUGGAGAGUGGCGGCAAAGACCGGCUGGAAGAGGACUUACAGGACGAUGAAAUAGAGAUGUUGGUUGAUGACCCCCGGGAUCUGGAGCAGAUGAAUGAAGAGUCUCUGGAAGUCAGCCCAGACAUGUGCAUCUACAUCACAGAGGACAUGCUCAUGUCGCGGAAGCUGAAUGGACACUCUGGGUUGAUUGUGAAAGAAAUUGGGUCUUCCACCUCGAGCUCUUCAGAAACAGUUGUUAAGCUUCGUGGCCAGAGUACUGAUUCUCUUCCACAGACUAUAUGUCGGAAACCAAAGACCUCCACUGAUCGACACAGCUUGAGCCUCGAUGACAUCAGACUUUACCAGAAAGACUUCCUGCGCAUUGCAGGUCUGUGUCAGGACACUGCUCAGAGUUACACCUUUGGAUGUGGCCAUGAACUGGAUGAGGAAGGCCUCUAUUGCAACAGUUGCUUGGCCCAGCAGUGCAUCAACAUCCAAGAUGCUUUUCCAGUCAAAAGAACCAGCAAAUACUUUUCUCUGGAUCUCACUCAUGAUGAAGUUCCAGAGUUUGUUGUGUAAAGUCCGUCUGUGUGCAGCUGUACAGGCAGCUUACUGUUUGCUAGAGGAUGCGAAAGUCAUAAGUUCUUUACAUAUUACUUGUGCCAUAUCUUCUUCACCCUAAACAUAGCUCUUUCUUUAUAAUAUUUGUGAUGAUGGAAACAAAAGCCUUGGAACAAUUGCACUUUAAGUAUUACACAGAAGUAAAAGAACUACAGAAAAUGUACAGCAAGACAAGUGCCCGGAAGUUCACUGAUCCUUCAGAAGGAAAUGCGCUUUACUGAUUGCAAAGCCUUCAGAAUAUUGGAGUGUGGUGUGUUUGCUCAUCUGAUGCUUUUUAGUUCAGUUACAUGUAACAUCACAUUUUUUUAUCACGUGAAAGAUGUUAGAUUUGUUUGCUUAUAAAUUUUUUACCACUCCCACAUAAAAUGCUCAUAGUUUGGGAGAGGAAAGAGGGAAGAUUCUCUCUUCUUUUAACAGAGAGAUGAUUGCUCUGUAUACCCAUUGCUUCCUCCCUGAGGCUGUCCCAAAGUGAACACUGAUGGAGUGGUCAAAAUCAUAAGGUUGUAGCAAGCCAAAGAUACGUAUGUGACAGAAGCACAUAAGCAAUAAGCAGAAAACCAGAAGUGCAUGCUGUGAUGCCUGUGACUCCUUCAUCCCGCUCAGUGCCAUGUCCUCUUUUGUGAUCUUCCAGAAAGCUCCAGGAUUCAUUUGAGUUCCACAUCCAAGUAACAGAUGAAUUAUAUUCAUGUUGUAAUGCAUUUUGUGGAGUUUACAAAACCAGUGUCUGUUAAAACUUUGGAAAAUGUCUUAGAAAACGUUGGUGCUUGGUGAUGCUUUAUUUGUUUAAUUAUCAAGAACAAAUUAUGGCAAUGCUAGUUUCUGCUUAACCAAAAUACUCUGUGUAUAUAUUAUACAUAUAUAAAUACAUGGGAUUGUGUAUGUCUAUAUGUGUUUAAAGCUUACUAUGUCUUCAUUUUGGCUUCCAUGACUAUCUUUUAUACAUGGAAUUCCUUAAGAUUGAGAAUAUGUCACUGAGUGAAUGAUACCUGCAGACAGUCAGUUGAUAUAUGUAGAGUUCAGAAUGACUGUUUUCUCAUGUGCCUUUGGCCAUGAUUCUCAACACUGAUUGUAUAACAGAAUUUUGGGGGGAGCUUUUAAAAAAUAAUGACUGAGUCUCCCACCAGACCGAUUACAUCAUUCUCUUGUGGCGGGACCCAAGUAGAAUUGCCUUUUCUUUUAAAGUUCUCCAGAUGGAGCUAAUAUGCAACAAAGUUGAAAACCACUGAUCCUGGGGGUGUCUUGUUAAUUUUGAAGUAAAAGUGUACAGAAGACGUAGUGUAUGAGAAAGGGCCAUUUUUAAGACAGUUACCUGUUGUGCUGCUGUUACAAUAUAUAAUGAAACCAAGUCAGGGGAGUGAAUUUAUCAAUCUUUUGAUGUAAAGUAAAAACGUAGUUCACACUUCAGGAGAGAACUUCAUAGCACAAUGUCUUUCUAUAAGAUAUUUUUAAUGAUUUAGUAUUUUACAACAUUUGUUUACCAUAUUUUGAUAUACCAUUUUUUUCUAUCUGCCCAGUUUUAUUAAAAAAACUAUAUAUUAUUUUCUAAAGAAACAAUCAUAUUUUUAUACAAAAUUAUGUUUUCAGGUAACGAAAUAGAUGUAGGGUACAGUGGAACAUAAGCAGUGUUACCCCUGGCUGGGAGUCAGUAUUAUACAACAAAUGGUGAGCUGGAACAUGCCCUGUCUGUGCUGUCCCUCCUGUGCUGGGUCGCGGAUGUGUAGGCAACAUUGCCUUAUCACGCUAGGUUCACCUGACACUUUAAAAGGAAAAAAAGUUCCAUAGAGUUCUGUGGUCACAAAAUUGUUUUGCUUUUAUCAAAUACUUUAAUAGAACCAAAGUUGCAGAUAUUGGAAUGUAUGGAAGUAUCUCAGUCUCUGCAUAAGAGGAUUAAAGUAUGAAAGGAUCAUUUAAUGACUGUUUUACUUAUAAGUCAUUAAGUAAUCCACCAUUUCUUAUGGAUGAUGCUUAAGCCUGGUGAGGUUUGUACUCUAAGGAGCCCAGAUCAUAAUGCAGUGCAUUUCCUUAGCCCUUAGAGUUUCUUGCAAACAUUUAAAAAAAGACAUAUUUAAGAAAGAAAGAUAAAGAAAAAACAUAUUUAAUUACUGUAAACAGGUACUGCUUUAUGUUUAUUUUCUCUCUACUUCAACCAAAAUCAGAUCUUUGAGGUUUUGCUGACAUUGUUGGUGGUUUUGCACAUGUUCUUUCUAAUUGGAUUUAUGAAUAGUUCUAUGGGUUUUCAAAGAUGAAUCAUGCUAAGAACACUUCUGCUUUUUGAUCCACUGUUUGCAGCAGAAUUAUAUAUAUGUAUAGGAAAAAUCCACUUUGAAUAAUCCAUGUUUUGUAUUUGGAAAUUGUUUUUAAAAAUAAAAAGGAAAGGAAAUAUAUAAAGCUGUUAUUUAUUCUGCAUUUCUUACAUAUCUAUCGCUUGUCAGUAUACCCGUUUUGGUAUAUAUUGCCUCUGCACAUCUACAUUUGUAUAUGCAACAGUGAGCUUUAUAUCUACAUAAACUGUAAAUAAUCCUUUCUGUGAAAGGAUCAUCAUAUCAAGAUGAUACCAAAAGUAUGUAAAAAGAAACCUGCAUUAUUUUGUAAUUAUUUCUUAUAGAUAUUUCAUGGUAAGAUUAGCAGUCAAUAAAGUUACUUUUUUGCCUUUAAA